GCUUAGAUGAGCUGGUUCAGUGUUGACGGAAGCUGAAGACAGACGGAAGCUCCACUACAACAUGUUCAGGGCGGCCCUCGAGGACAGCGUGGAGAAGAAAUCCUCCCUGAAGGAAACAGAAACAACAUCCAAAGGAACCAGCAAGUAUGACAGAGAGAGAGAGACAGAGAUGAAGACAGUCAUGGGAAUGAAGAUGCAUUUUUGGGCGGCCCCGCUCCCUCUGCUGGCCAUGGCCCCCCCGCCCGCGUGCCGGUCCCCGAUGUCACCGCCGCCGCCGCCGCUGCUGCUGCUGCUGCUGAGUCUGGCGCUGCUGGGCGCCCGGGCCCGCGCCGAGCCCGCCGGGAGUGCCGUCCCCGCGCAGAGCCGCCCAUGCGUGGACUGCCACGCCUUCGAGUUCAUGCAGCGCGCCCUGCAGGACCUGCGGAAGACAGCCUGCAGCCUGGACGCGCGGACGGAGACCCUACUGCUGCAGGCAGAGCGCCGUGCCCUGUGUGCCUGCUGGCCAGCGGGGCACUGAGGACCACGCUGCUCCGUGUGAAUAAAUGCCCAGUGGCA